GCGAGCCAGCGGCCAGGCGACCGGCGGGCGGCCAGCCAGCGAGCCGAACUAGCCGAGCUAGGUAGCGAGGCGUGCGCGUGGGCCGGGGCGGCGGCGCCCCCAUCCCCAGCACCGAGGGGCGAGCAUGGCCCGCCCGCGGGGGGGCUGGACCGCCGCGCACGCCGCCCGAUCCCCGCGCCCUACCCAGCCCGGGUCGCCGCCGCUCGCGCCCGCCGCUUAGCGCUCGGGCGCCGCUCGCUUCUCCGGGCAUCGCGGAAAUCCCGCCGCAGACGGACACAAUGGCGGCGGCGGCGGCGGCCGCCACCACGGCCGCCUGCAGCAGCGGCAGCGCCGGCACCGACGCCGCGGGCGCCAGCGGAUUGCAGCAGCCGCCGCCGCAGCCCCAGCCUCAGCCCGCGGCCGCCGCGCCGGCCCAGCCGCCGCCCGAACCCCCCCGGAAGCCGCGCAUGGACCCGCGGCGCCGCCAGGCUGCCCUCUCCUUCCUCACCAACAUCUCGCUGGACGGCCGGCUGCCGCCGCAGGACGCGGAGUGGGGCGGUGGCGAGGAGGGCGGCGCGGCCAAGCCGGGCGCCGGCGGCGCCUGCGGCGCGAGGACUCGGUUCAGCUUGCUCGCCGCUGCCGAGCGGGGCGGCUGCAUCGCGCUCGCCGCGCCGGGCACGCCGGCUGCGGGGUUAGCCGCUGGGUCCGGCCCCUGCCUCCCACAGCCCUCGUCGCUGCCGCCCUUGAUUCCUGGCGGCCAUGCGACCGUGUCCGGCCCCGGGGUGGCGCGGGGGUUCGCGAGUCCCCUGGGCGCCGGCCGGGCGUCGGGGGAGCAGUGGCAGCCGCCCCGGCCGGCGCCUCUCGCCGCCUGUGCCCAACUGCAGCUGCUCGACGGGUCCGGGGCCGCCGGGCAGGAGGAGUUGGAGGAGGACGAUGCCUUUAUCAGCGUGCAGGUGCCGGCGGCCGCCUUUUUGGGCUCCGGGACCCCCGGGAGUGGGAGCGGCAGUCGGGGACGCCUCAACUCGUUCACUCAGGGAAUCCUGCCCAUCGCCUUCUCCAGGCCGACUUCGCAGAACUACUGCUCCCUGGAGCAGCCAGGCCAGGGCGGCAGCACCAGCGCCUUCGAGCAGCUGCAGAGGUCCCGACGGCGCCUCAUCUCCCAGAGAUCUUCCUUGGAGACCCUGGAAGAUAUUGAGGAGAACGCCCCUCUCCGGAGAUGUCGAACUCUCUCAGGUUCACCCAGACCAAAGAAUUUUAAGAAGAUUCAUUUUAUCAAGAACAUGCGGCAACACGAUACCAGGAAUGGCAGAAUAGUCCUUAUCAGUGGCAGAAGAUCCUUCUGUAGUAUAUUUUCAGUGCUGCCGUAUCGCGACAGUACCCAAGUCGGGGACUUGAAGUUGGACGGAGGAAGACAAUCAACUGGUGCAGUGAGUUUGAAAGAGAUCAUUGGUCUGGAAGGUGUGGAGCUGGGUGCUGAUGGGAAGACUGUUUCCUAUACCCAAUUUCUGUUACCCACAAAUGCCUUUGGAGCCCGGAGAAAUACCAUAGACUCCACCUCCUCUUUCUCCCAGUUCCGUAACCUGAGCCACCGCAGCCUCUCCAUAGGCCGGGCAAGCGGCACCCAGGGGAGCCUCGACACAGGUAGUGACCUGGGAGACUUUAUGGACUAUGACCCAAAUCUCUUGGAUGACCCCCAGUGGCCUUGUGGCAAACACAAACGCGUUCUGAUCUUCCCUUCCUACAUGACAACAGUGAUUGACUACGUGAAGCCCUCGGAUCUCAAGAAGGACAUGAACGAGACCUUCAAGGAGAAGUUUCCUCACAUUAAGCUGACACUCAGCAAAAUUAGGAGUCUGAAACGAGAGAUGCGGAAGCUUGCGCAGGAGGACUGUGGCCUUGAGGAGCCCACGGUGGCCAUGGCCUUCGUCUACUUUGAAAAGCUCGCCCUCAAGGGGAAACUCAACAAACAGAACCGGAAGCUGUGUGCUGGGGCAUGUGUGCUGUUAGCAGCCAAAAUUGGAAGUGACCUCAAAAAACACGAAGUCAAGCAUUUAAUUGACAAACUGGAAGAGAAGUUCCGGCUGAACAGGCGAGAACUGAUUGCCUUUGAAUUCCCGGUGUUAGUGGCCUUGGAAUUCGCCCUCCACUUGCCCGAGCACGAAGUCAUGCCCCACUACAGACGGCUGGUCCAGAGUUCCUAGCACUGGCCCCGAGGACAGCCAAGGGCCAUUUCUUCUCAGCUUGGUGGAGCAGCACUUACUUACUACUGGAAAUGAAAAAAAGUAGAACUCAGAAUACCAGACUUUUCUUCCUCUCGACAUAGUUUGGGGAGAAGCAGUACUAGAAACUUUCCAAGGAGUCUUGGGUGUGUAGCCAAGAGGAGCCAUGAGCUAUGGACUCCUCAAGCACGGGAAGAGGAGGUGUGUGCUGAGAACAGAGAGGCCCUGCCCUCUGUCCACUAGCGAGAAUCCCUAGCUGCCCCAGCCCAGUCUUUCUCCCCGGCAUUCACAAACUUUGCAAGCGUGGUCCAGGGCCUUCUCCAGAUCUGUUCCAACUUGGAGUGUGAAGGGCUUGAGCAUACGGGGGAAGAGAGUCUGCAGAAGUUGGGGGAAAACUUUUAAAAGAUACCCUCAUUGUGUCAAAGAGUGUGCCAAUCUAUUUUUGUAUCAGCAUUGGAAGUGCACUUUCCCCUGGGGCGUGUGGGUGUGUGAAUGUGCAAGUGUCUGAGAGAUACUGCAUCAGCCCUAGACCCCCAGAGCCAGUCCCGCCCUUUACAGAGCAGCCCUUAGCCUGGGGCCAUGGGUCAGGCUGACCUUCAACAAUUAUUUCUAGAUGAUUUCUGGAUAAGAAUUGCUCUCUCGGUACCAGACAGUUUGACAUCCUCCACCCUUAGAAAAUGACUGACAUUGUUUUGUUACUGCUCCUACCCACCAAGGGGAUAAAGAAGGCGAGUUCUGAGUGUUGGAUGAGUCAGUCGCGUGGAAGGACGUGGAGCGUGGCGCUCUGUAACUUCCUGCCGUCUGCCACCCCGCCACGUGUAUUUAACCCUCGCACUUUCUCCACUGUGGAGAUGGCUGGGGCGGCGCCCCACAGUGUGUAUUCCUGUCCUCUAUGUUAGAGUGCAUCAGAAGCACAUUUACUGUGCUAUCUAUAUCGCUAUAUAAAAGUGUUUUAUAAAAACCCAGAAUAGGAGCACGACGCAUGAUUGGUGUUUGAGGCGUUUGCCAGCUGGGACAAACUGCGUUUGGAGCUGUGGUUAAGCUGACUAAGGAGGCGGUGGCUCUUUCUUAACAUUCCCACGUGCCCAGGGCUGUUCAUGCAAGAUUUUAAUGGUGACUUGUCCUGGCUUACUGGGACAGUCUGUAUGAGGCAUGUCACCACACUGUCGCCUCAUAGCUGCAAGAGAGAGGCACCAGCUGAAGUUCCCCUGACUGAAGAGAGCCUGUGGCCAUGUAAAAAGAGAAUUAAACUCUUGUUGCUUUUUGUAUACCUGUAUGCGUUUGUGUAGACGUGUGUCUCACCAGUCACCUUUGCCCUGCAUUGCUGAUCCCCUUGCGCACACUGAUUCUAGUGAGGUCACAGAUUCGGAGCUUCACACACCAGCCCAGAGAAAGGGCGAUGGAACCGAACCGAGGGUCUGCAGCUUUCGUUAGCAGAGCUGUCAGAUUCUUGACAGUCUUGGAGGAUGGAGAAAUUCAAGCAGCAGCUGGUGAGGGCCAAAACAGAAUACUUGGCUUCUUCAGAAUCUUAGAUUGCACUGAGUUUAGUCCUAAAUAUUUUGCUAACAAAUUUCCUUGGCCAGAAUCAGUUGUAAGACAGUGAUUUGGGUGGUGGGGGGAGGGAGGAGGGAGAGGAUAUGAUUAAUGUGGUCUCUUUGGCUGAUCGAAAGCUAGAUCAACUGGUACUUAGGGCACUUGCUGUUUAUAAAGCAAAAUUGAGAAAAUAUUCAAGGUGCCUCCAUCGCCUGAACUACAAAAUGCCCUUGGCCUUCCUCACAUGGGGUCUGUCACCUUGCAUCUCUGAUAAGCCAUCCACCUUCCUGGUCAGUGCCUACAGGGGGAGAGCCUUUCUGAGAAGCAGGUCCUGUGGUAUCUGAGAAUGGUCUAGAGAGCUCCCCACUGCCCAUCUGCCCCCGAAUUUCCUGCCAAGCUCUGGGGAGUGGGGUGGGGGGAGGGACGUCCGAUGGAUGACAGGCCGCCAGCCCAGACGUGGGGAGAGAAGCCUGAGUCCUUUCCUGUGUGAUAAAAUCAGGCUAAUUUACUUGGAUUUGGGGUGAUUUGUUUGGUUUUUAGCAUUUAUGAGGUGAGCCCAUGAAGUUAGUGGUCCAUUACUUUUUAAAGAUGCAUUUUCAUUUUAAACUGUCUCCUGGCCUGUGGAUUUGUGGAAUGGACAGUUUUGUGGGUUUUAAUUUAUUUGUGAGGAGUCGGGGCUGAGAAGGCAUUUUAUCAGGAGGUCUCCUUUUGCACGUCCAUGACAUGAGCUUUUCGGAGGCAAAGGAAGUGGAGGAGGGUGAGAGAUGCAGGUCACUGCCAGAGGCACCUCUGUGACACGGAACAUUCCAGACACGUCGCAGCCUUGGGCUUCGGCGAGGAGGAAGUCUGAGCCUGUGAAGCGAGAAGGCCAGGCAGUAGACUGGCUCUGAGGUUUUGCCCUUUGACCUCCUCCACAGAGGGCAGCUUCAGCCCCUUGUAAGCCCUGCCCCCUCUCAGGACUGCCCUGAGGCCUCUCCAGUCCUCCCCACACUCAGAGAUCUGUGGGGAAGCUCCGCCCAGCCACACUCCUUGGGAUAAUACUAGCCGGUUCUGCCUGAUUCCUUUUCCCCCGGAGCCAGCCUAGGGGGCCCGGGACUCCUCUAGUGAGCCUUGACUGUUAGGUAAGAGACAGGAAGCAGACAAGCCAAGAGGUUGCUGCAGCUGCCCCCAGGAGGAAACGGGCAGCAGGGAGUGUGGCCCAGCCCCCACUGUACCCCUCCAGGGGCCCGAGCCCUUGCCAGCCCAAUGACACCUUGAAGUCACCACUUUUCCUUUCUUGCCCGCUAAUAAAACCUAUUUAAACAGGAAAUUCAUACCAAAUGCAAAUGGGUUUUGUUUUCCUUGGCAUUUUGUUGUUCCGAUCACAGAUUUCCCUGCCAGGGUGUCUGUGGUUAUCAGCUGCAGGCUCAGCUUGGGGCGGCCGCUUCACACAAGCCACUCUGUACCACGUGCCCUACCUUAGUGACGGGAGUAAGGAGCUUCCUUCCCCUCCAUGUCAUUCCUUCCUGUUCCCUUCAUUCCCCAACAGCAAAUAAAACUGUUGAAUGCUCUG